GCAAUCUGGAAGGGUGGUACUCAGAUUAGGUGCACCACGCAUGGGUUCUUCUCCUCCACUUCCCAUUGUUUUUGAGCAAUUGCAGGAUUUUCAAAUUAGCCAAUAAUGAGUAAUAUUCAGCGAGGCUCACAGCUUUGGCAUGUAGAUACAGAUUUUGCUACAAGCUGGGAAGAAUAAUUCCUCUUCUGGCACUGUCCCUUGUUACUCUCAGUCAUAGAAUUUCAUAAUAUUUUAGCAAGUGCUGAGAACUAUGUAUCUAGAUCACAGCGGAAGCCUUCAUGAGUGCAUAUGUACCGUACUUACCUUUUUUUUUUUUCUGGUUAGAAGGAAGGCUUUACUUUUACAGCCAAGUUUUUGUUGUGAGAGAAAUCAAAGGAUUCCAACAGUUUUAAUAAUCUACAGAAGGAUUCUUUUCCAGGCAUCCAACGCACUGGAGGAGCUUUGCUUUAUGAUUAUGGGAAUGCUACCAAAGCCUCAGGAACAAGAUGAAAAAGAUAAUACUAAAAGGUUCUUAUUUCAUUAUUCGAAGACACAGAAGUUGGGCAAGUCAAAUGUUGUGUCGUCAGUUGUGCAUCCGUUGCUGCAGCUCGUUCCUCACCUGCAUGAGAGAAGAAUGAAGAGAUUCAGAGUGGACGAAGAAUUCCAAAGUCCCUUUGCAAGUCAAAGUCGAGGAUAUUUUUUAUUCAGGCCACGGAAUGGAAGAAGGUCAGCAGGGUUCAUUUAAAAUGGAUGCCAGCUAAUUUUCCACAGAGCAAUGCUAUGGAAUACAAAAUGUACUGACAUUUUGUUUUCUUCUGAAAAAAAUCCUUGCUAAAUGUACUCUGUUGAAAAUCCCUGUGUUGUCAAUGUUCUCAGUUGUAACAAUGUUGUAAAUGUUCAAUUUGUUGAAAAUUAAAAAAUCUAAAAAUA